AGAUGAGGCUGCUAAGCCGAAUGUGUUGUUACUCCUUUACAUCGUCUCUCCACAUGGCUUGAACUUCUCACAGCAUGCCUGCUGGAUUCGAAGAGAUGGCAUUCAAGUGCUUAAAAAUCAAGAAGACCCUCACCAGGUGCCAGCGUCUAGACAUUGGAUUUUCCAGCCUCCAGAACUUACUUCUAGUCUAGUUGGAGAAACAACCUAGAAAAUGCACCAACAAAUGGGGCACAAUAACUACUCUGAGAGAGAGUGGCACACAGUGGACGCAAAGAAGAGGUUCCUGAUGCAGCUGGGAAGAGUCUACAUGGGCCUCUAGCAGGAGAAGAUACUGGUCUUGAGUUUGGAGACUAAGUAAGCAUCUCCAGUGUCGAAUAGGUACCUGGGUCAACUCCACACACUUCUCACUCUUCACUGGACCUCUGGUACAAGAUUGAGAGGAUUCCUAUUACUUACAAACAGACUAGUUCAUCUGGCUCUCCAUGAAUGUCCUGCUUUUCUGGAAAACCUUCUUGCUGUAUAACCAAGGGCCAGAGUAUCACUACCUCCACCAGAUGUUGGGGCUAGGAUUGUGUCUAAGCAGAGCCUCAGCAUCUGUUCUUAACCUCAACUGCAGCCUUAUCCUUUUACCCAUGUGCCGAACACUCUUGGCUUACCUCCGAGGAUCACAGAAGGUUCCAAGCAGGAGAACCAGGAGAUUGUUGGAUAAAAGCAGAACAUUCCAUAUUACCUGUGGUGUUACUAUCUGUAUUUUCUCAGGCGUGCAUGUGGCUGCCCAUCUGGUGAAUGCCCUCAACUUCUCAGUGAAUUACAGUGAAGACUUUGUUGAACUGAAUGCAGCAAGAUACCGAGAUGAGGAUCCUAGAAAACUUCUCUUCACAACUGUUCCUGGCCUGACAGGGGUCUGCAUGGUGGUGGUGCUAUUCCUCAUGAUCACAGCCUCUACAUAUGCAAUAAGAGUUUCUAACUAUGAUAUCUUCUGGUAUACUCAUAACCUCUUCUUUGUCUUCUACAUGCUGCUGACGUUGCAUGUUUCAGGAGGGCUGCUGAAGUAUCAAACUAAUUUAGAUACCCACCCUCCCGGCUGCAUCAGUCUUAACCGAACCAGCUCUCAGAAUAUUUCCUUACCAGAGUAUUUCUCAGAACAUUUUCAUGAACCUUUCCCUGAAGGAUUUUCAAAACCGGCAGAGUUUACCCAGCACAAAUUUGUGAAGAUUUGUAUGGAAGAGCCCAGAUUCCAAGCUAAUUUUCCACAGACUUGGCUUUGGAUUUCUGGACCUUUGUGCCUGUACUGUGCCGAAAGACUUUACAGGUAUAUCCGGAGCAAUAAGCCAGUCACCAUCAUUUCGGUCAUGAGUCAUCCCUCAGAUGUCAUGGAAAUCCGAAUGGUCAAAGAAAAUUUUAAAGCAAGACCUGGUCAGUAUAUUACUCUACAUUGUCCCAGUGUAUCUGCAUUAGAAAAUCAUCCAUUUACCCUCACAAUGUGUCCAACUGAAACCAAAGCAACAUUUGGGGUUCAUCUUAAAAUAGUAGGAGACUGGACAGAACGAUUUCGAGAUUUACUACUGCCUCCAUCUAGUCAAGACUCCGAAAUUCUGCCCUUCAUUCAAUCUAGAAAUUAUCCCAAGCUGUAUAUUGAUGGUCCUUUUGGAAGUCCAUUUGAGGAAUCACUGAACUAUGAGGUCAGCCUCUGCGUGGCUGGAGGCAUUGGAGUAACUCCAUUUGCAUCAAUACUCAACACCCUGUUGGAUGACUGGAAACCAUACAAGCUUAGAAGACUAUACUUUAUUUGGGUAUGCAGAGAUAUCCAGUCCUUCCGUUGGUUUGCAGAUUUACUCUGUAUGUUGCAUAACAAGUUUUGGCAAGAGAACAGACCUGACUAUGUCAACAUCCAGCUGUACCUCAGUCAAACAGAUGGGAUACAGAAGAUAAUUGGAGAAAAAUAUCAUGCACUGAAUUCAAGACUGUUUAUAGGACGUCCUCGGUGGAAACUUUUGUUUGAUGAAAUAGCAAAAUAUAACAGAGGAAAAACAGUUGGUGUUUUCUGUUGUGGACCCAAUUCACUAUCCAAGACUCUUCAUAAACUGAGUAACCAGAACAACUCAUAUGGGACAAGAUUUGAAUACAAUAAAGAGUCUUUCAGCUGAAAACUUUUGCCAUGAAGCAGGACUCUAAAGAAGGAAUGAGUGCAAUUUCUAAGACUUUGAAACUCAGCGGAAUCAAUCAGCUGUGUUAUGCCAAAGAAUAGUAAGGUUUUCUUAUUUAUGAUUAUUUAAAAUGGAAAUGUGAGAAUGUGGCAAGAUGACCGUCACAUUACAUGUUUAAUCUGGAAACCAAAGAGACCCUGAAGAAUAUUUGAUGUGAUGAUUCACUUUUCAGUUCUCAAAUUAAAAGAAAACUGUUAGAUGCACACUGUUGAUUUUCAUGGUGGAUUCAAGAACUCCCUAGUGAGGAGCUGAACUUGCUCAAUCUAAGGCUGAUUGUCGUGUUCCUCUUUAAAUUGUUUUUGGUUGAACAAAUGCAAGAUUGAACAAAAUUAAAAAUUCAUUGAAGCUGAAAUUCCAUUUUCUGUGUUGUGUAUAAACAGAGUAGCUUUAAUUUGCAAGCACUCCAGGCAAAUAUAUUAGAUGUUUGAAAACACAGCACAAGACUCUGUAUUGAUACGGGUACUUUGUGUCAAUAUCUAAUCGUCUCCACUACUUAUGCUAAUACCUCUAUUUGAUAUCUGAAGACUAUAUGCUAACUGAACCUUCCUCAAAUGUUGUUAUAGUAUCUAUUUUUAUAUAUUUUUUUCUUUUUAUUCCUCUCUCUAGGGAAAUAUGCCUUCCCUUAGCAUGCAUUAGACAUAAUGAUUUAAUAGGUCCCUUUCAUCUUCAUUUAAAUCUAUCACUAUUGCAUGGUAAUGAAAAUAUUCCUACUAUAAAUUAUAAAGGGAUAUAUAUAUAUGGAUAUAUAUAUGUAUAUACACAUAUAUAUAUACACACACACACACAUAUAUAUAUAUAUAUAUAUAUAUACACAUAUACUAAUAACUUUUCCCUUUUUUCAGCAUUUUUGUCUCUAUUAUUAUUAUUGUUUUUUUCCCAGGUAGGGUUUGUCUUAGGCUGUAGCCUCUAAGGAUAGUUAGUUAAUUUGCACUUUGAGACCAAAGGACAUCAUGUGUGUCAGUAGGGACUGAAUAUAAGAUUUAUCUCCUUUGCCACACAUUGGUUUAUGAUGGAGACAUUGAAAGUCUAGUCAUAUUCCUGAACAGUAAAACCUGUAUUUUACCUUUUAAGUAAGAGGAAAUAUGAUAUUCUUAUUCAAACUUAAGUUUAGAAUCCAGAAUAUUACUGUCGCACUUUUUGGUAUCCUGAGUUUCCAUAGGGAACUAUUGGGUUUAAAGUCACCGUUGGAACUACACUGUGUGAUCUUAUAAACUUAUGUUCCCUGGCUAUCAUAUUCUUGGCUCAGAACAAUAUUUCCCAUUACUAUCUUAAGAAUUAAGGCAUUCAUGGCUCACGCCUGUAAUCCCGGCACUUUGGGAGGCCAAGGCAGGUGGAUCACGAGGUCAGAGUUCAAGACCAGCCUGACCAAGUUGGUGAAACCCCAUCGCUACUAAAAAUACAAAUAUUAGGCGGGUGUGGUGGCGGGUGCCUAUAAUCCCAACUACUCGGGAGACUGAGGCAAAGAAUCGCUUGAACCCGGUGGGCGGAGGUUGCAGUGAGCCAAGAUUGCACCACUGCACUCCAGCCUGGGUGACAGAGCAAGAUUCCAUCUCAAAAAAAAAAAAAAAAAAAAAAAAAAAGAAUUAAAGCAUUCAUACAGUUUAGUGAUUUUGUUUAGUAGUCGGCUAUCAAUUGCUAUCAAAUAUAACACUGCUGAAAUCAGCAGUGUGACUUACCUUGCCAUUGUUAAAAUGUUACAUAAAACAUAACAUGAUAGAUGCUAAGGCCUUUUUUUGCUAUAAUUCACCAAUAGCAAUCAAGCAUGCUAACCCAUACUGAAUGAUAUUUACUUGUAGAUAUUUCUUCCUUUCCUUGAAAUUCUCCUUUCUAUGGAAAGAAGAUGAACCCAAAAAAGUGAUAGGAAAUGUGGAAUGCUCAUGCAGAUUUAGCUCUGAAGGCAUAUUUAAUAACUAGUAUGUCUUGACAACAGUCUUUAGAUUAAAAAGAAUUUUCAUGGAAACAUUUAACAGAAAGAACUAGUAAAAAGACACUUUGAGUUAGUCCAGGCUUAAUGUGCAAUACUGACUCUAUACUGAUCAUAAUUUAUUUAUGCGAUCAUAUUAAUAGACCUAAUUUCAUUAAAACAGGUAGAAGAUUUUUCAAAAGAAAGAUGAUGUUUCAAAGCUGGUCUGCCAUUCUAGAUGAGCCUCCUUGCUUAUUUAAGUUCCAGUAGGUGUUCAAAUGUUAAAUGUUAAACAUAGGUCAUCUUUGCUUCUGCAGGGCUUCAUCUUGCAUGUUUAAGAGAACUUUGUUUUAUUUUGAGGGAUUAUUUCUCUGGGGAUCAUUCUUAUAAUACAAGCCUUAAAUCACUAAUUUUAGUAGCAAUAAAUGUUAAAAUUGAAA